GGAGCGGCUGGGGCUGCGGCGCCGCUGCUGACACGGAUCGGCCGCGGCCGCCACCGGGCGGAGGCUGCGCGGCGCAGACCCAGACGGGCGGCCCCGGAGGGCGCGCGGCGAUGGCGGCGGCGGGCAGGCGGCGGGCGCGGCGGGCGAGGGGUCCGGGCUGAGCUGCGGGCCGGCCCGGAUGGCGGGCGGCGCGGGCUGGUCGGGCGCCCCCGCGGCUCUGCUGCGCUCCGUGCGCCGCCUGCGCGAGGUGUUCGAGGUGUGCGGCCGCGACCCCGACGGCUUCCUGCGCGUGGAGCGCGUCGCGGCGCUCGGACUGCGCUUCGGCCAGGGCGAGGAGGUGGAAAAACUUGUGAAAUAUUUGGAUCCCAACGACCUGGGGAGAAUCAACUUCAAGGACUUUUGCCGGGGGGUGUUCGCCAUGAAAGGGUGCGAGGAGCUGCUGAAGGAUGUGCUGUCGGUGGAGAGCGCGGGGACGCUGCCGUGCGCGCCAGAGAUCCCAGACUGCGUGGAGCAGG